AGAACAAGCGGUCAUGUGACUGGGAAGAUGGCCGUCUUUCCUUGGCACUCCAGGAAUAGGAACUACAAAGCUGAAUUUGCAUCAUGCCGACUGGAGGCUGUACCAUUGGAGUUUGGGGACUAUCACCCUCUGAAACCCAUAACUGUCACAGAGUCAAAGACAAAGAAAGUGAACCGGAAAGGAAGCACUUCUUCCACGUCCUCCUCCUCCUCCAGCUCCGUGGUGGACCCGCUGAGCAGCGUCCUCGAUGGGACUGACCCCCUCUCCAUGUUUGCAGCCACUGCUGACCCCGCAGCCUUGGCAGCUGCCAUGGACAGCUCCAGAAGGAAACGUGAUAGAGAUGAUAACUCCGUUGUAGGAUCGGAUUUUGAGCCUUGGACCAACAAACGGGGAGAAAUCCUUGCCCGGUACACCACUACCGAAAAGCUGUCUAUUAAUCUGUUUAUGGGAUCUGAAAAAGGCAAAGCUGGGACUGCCACAUUGGCAAUGUCAGAGAAGGUGCGGACCCGGCUGGAGGAGCUGGAUGACUUUGAGGAGGGUUCCCAAAAGGAGCUGUUGAACUUGACUCAGCAGGAUUACGUGAACCGCAUAGAGGAGCUCAACCAAUCGCUGAAGGAUGCCUGGGCCUCAGACCAGAAAGUGAAGGCUCUAAAAAUAGUCAUCCAGUGUUCAAAGCUUCUUUCAGACACCAGUGUUAUUCAGUUCUACCCAAGCAAAUUUGUCCUUAUCACCGACAUACUUGAUACAUUUGGAAAGCUCGUGUACGAGCGCAUCUUUUCCAUGUGUGUGGAUAGCCGCAGCGUCUUACCAGAUCACUUUUCUCCAGAGAAUGCAAAUGACACGGCCAAGGAAACAUGCCUAAAUUGGUUUUUCAAGAUUGCCUCCAUCAGGGAACUCAUUCCAAGAUUUUACGUGGAGGCAUCCAUCCUGAAAUGUAACAAAUUCCUCUCCAAAACGGGAAUUUCAGAGUGCCUGCCCCGGUUGACAUGCAUGAUCAGAGGGAUCGGAGACCCACUAGUGUCGGUGUAUGCCCGUGCCUACCUGUGCCGGCAGAGGCCAAAGUGUGUAUGCAUCGCCCACUGCUUGAAACCUGGGGGGGAUUUUCCAUCCAGAGAUAUCAGGUGGGAAUGGAAGUGGCCCCACAUCUCAAAGAAACCCUAAAUAAGAACUUUUUUGACUUCCUCCUUACGUUCAAACAGAUUCAUGGGGAUACGGUCCAGAACCAGCUGGUGGUCCAAGGAGUGGAGCUCCCAUCUUACCUCCCCUUGUACCCGCCUGCCAUGGACUGGAUCUUCCAGUGCAUCUCCUACCAUGCCCCCGAGGCUCUGCUGACCGAGAUGAUGGAAAGGUGUAAGAAACUAGGAAACAAUGCCUUGCUGUUGAAUUCUGUGAUGUCUGCCUUCCGGGCUGAGUUCAUCGCCACAAGGUCUAUGGAUUUCAUUGGCAUGAUUAAAGAGUGUGAUGAAUCUGGUUUCCCCAAGCAUCUUCUUUUUCGAUCACUGGGAUUAAACUUGGCCUUGGCUGAUCCUCCUGAGAGUGACCGACUUCAGAUUCUCAACGAAGCUUGGAAAGUCAUCACUAAGCUGAAGAACCCACAGGACUACAUUAAUUGUGCCGAAGUGUGGGUGGAAUACACCUGCAAGCAUUUCACGAAACGAGAGGUGAAUACCGUUUUGGCAGAUGUCAUCAAGCACAUGACUCCAGAUCGUGCAUUUGAAGAUUCCUACCCCCAGCUUCAGUUAAUAAUUAAGAAAGUUAUUGCCCACUUCCAUGACUUCUCAGUUCUUUUCUCAGUGGAAAAAUUUCUGCCGUUUCUGGACAUGUUCCAAAAAGAGAGUGUGCGGGUGGAGGUUUGCAAAUGCAUCAUGGACGCCUUUAUCAAGCAUCAACAAGAGCCCACCAAGGACCCGGUCAUCUUGAAUGCCCUUUUGCAUGUUUGCAAGACCAUGCAUGACUCUGUGAAUGCACUCACUCUUGAGGAUGAGAAAAGAAUGCUGUCAUAUUUGAUUAAUGGAUUUAUAAAAAUGGUUUCCUUUGGCCGUGAUUUUGAACAACAGCUGAGUUUUUAUGUUGAGUCCAGGUCGAUGUUUUGCAAUCUGGAGCCUGUUCUUGUGCAGUUGAUUCAUAGUGUGAACCGGUUGGCAAUGGAGACAAGAAAAGUAAUGAAAGGAAAUCAUUCCAGAAAGACAGCUGCAUUUGUCCGGGCCUGUGUUGCCUACUGCUUCAUCACCAUCCCCUCCCUGGCGGGCAUCUUCACACGUCUCAAUCUCUACCUGCAUUCUGGUCAGGUGGCCUUGGCCAACCAGUGCCUCUCCCAAGCUGAUGCUUUUUUCAAAGCCGCUAUAAGCCUUGUUCCGGAAGUUCCAAAGAUGAUUAAUAUUGAUGGGAAGAUGCGGCCAUCGGAAUCGUUCCUUCUGGAAUUCCUCUGCAAUUUCUUUUCUACUUUAUUAAUAGUUCCGGAUCAUCCUGAACAUGGGGUCCUGUUUCUUGUUCGAGAGCUUCUCAACGUGAUCCAGGACUACACCUGGGAGGACAACAGCGAUGAGAAAAUCCGCAUCUACACCUGCGUCCUGCAUCUCCUCUCCGCCAUGAGCCAGGAGACGUACCUUUACCACAUAGACAAAGUGGACUCCAACGACAGCCUCUACGGGGGAGACUCCAAGUUCCUGGCAGAAAACAACAAGCUGUGUGAGACGGUGAUGGCUCAGAUCCUAGAGCAUCUGAAAACCCUGGCCAAGGACGAGGCCCUGAAGCGCCAGAGCUCGUUGGGCCUUUCCUUCUUUAACAGCAUCUUGGCCCAUGGGGACCUACGCAACAACAAGCUCAACCAGCUCUCCGUCAACCUGUGGCACCUGGCACAGAGGCACGGCUGUGCAGACACCAGGACCAUGGUGAAAACGCUAGAAUACAUCAAGAAGCAAAGCAAACAACCAGACAUGACUCAUCUGACGGAGCUGGCCCUCAGACUCCCUCUGCAAACAAGGACCUGACCCCCGGGCCCAUCCCCAGGCUCAGGGACUCUGGUGCCAAAUCCAGAAAGAUCUGCUCUGCUGCCCUGAACUCUUACGGCAAUUUAGGUUUCUCAUUUUUCUUUUCUUUUUACAUAUGUACAAAUUGUUUUAAGCUUUGGCCUCUAUCCAGGUUAUUCUGACAAUGAAGAAAUGGGAGUUGUCAGAGCAUUAAAAUGCAAUCUUCACUAAGAAGCAGUCUCUGUGUUGUCUUUGCACAAGUGGCCUUCGGUCUACUCAGCCCGAUCUGAUGGGCCUUUUUAGCAAGAGAGAAACAAGAAUGCAAGUAACAUCUUUCUUCUCUGGAAGGUGUUUGUUUUUUCAUAGUUUAGAAAUAAGGACUUUAAAAGUGGACUGCUUUUCAAAGUGCCACUGUUCCAGACCCAUUCCAUUCCAGACUUUGUACCUUAAAGUUAGAGCACACCCAAAGUCUGGAACUGUGUUACCUGAACCCCUAUGGAGGAUUUAUAAAAGGCAGAAAUAGCACUCCAUUAACUCUUUUUCCUAUCAAAAGCAGCUCUUGAUUGGACUUAGAAUCUGUGUUGGUGGAUCAAAGGAGAAAGCGAGGUCAAAUUUGAGAUUCUCUGUGGCUUCAGUAUACAGUAACUGAAUAAAUGUCCUGAAGGAGCAUUUAUGUUCAUGACUGUUCAUUUAAUUACUUCUGACUGU